GCACAGACUUGUCUUACAGUGAAAGCGACUUGGUGAAUUUUAUUCAAGCAAAUUUUAAGAAACGAGAAUGUGUCUUCUUUACCAAAGAUUCCAAGGCCACGUAAGCUACUAUUUUCCCUCCAGUUUUGCUUUCCAAGUUCAAAAAAAUUAUCAGCCACCCUUACAACAAACAAAUGCUCCCUAGUUCAUUAUUAAAGAUGUCUUCGUCUUAUAAUUCUCAGAAACACUGUUUGCGCAGGAAGGAUCUGGCAAGGAGCUUAUAGUUGUUACUCAGAGCUAUACAAUUUUGUUUGGUAUUUUCAGCUUUGGCCAUAGUUGGAAAAGUCGUUGAGGGAGGCUGUCACUCUCUUCAGUAUUCCCAUGAGAUUGGGAACCCACCUGAGUGACCUUGGUAAUGAAAGUUGUUUUACAGCUGUUGGCUGGCAAUACCAUGCAUGUGUACAUAUGUCCAUCUUACUGGCUCCUCCGUCAGGCUUUUCUUCCCUGCUGUUGACUUUAGGUCUUUCCUUCUAAUUGAGUGUUCAUCUGCUCUAAGUCUCAUGUGUUUUGGAACAUUAAGGCUGGGUUACAAAAGCAGGCUUCACCAGCUCAGCCUACAGGAGUUCUUCAAUAACUGUUGAUGAGCAAGUGAGUGAGUGAAUGGGUCGACUAGUGCUCACCCUUUGUGUAGAAGAUGCAUUUGAAUCUAAUUAAACAAUUUUCGUCCUACCUCCCACUCUCCUUAUUCCUCUCUGCCCCUUCCUUUCUGUUGGCUGGCAAUGCAAGAAAGAGUCUAGCUAUUAAUUGCAAGUUGCUGCUGUAGUUUAUAAUGAAAAGACUCUCUGUUGAACAGGGUCAAUGAACAGAGGAAGGAUAUAGAAAUAAGGAAAAAAGCUUUAGAACCAGCUUUGGUUUCAACCUUGACUUGGCUGACUCCUCACUGUGUGGCCUUGAGCCAAUUAUUCUCUUUUCUAAAGCUAAUUCUCUUAUCCUAAAAAUCUAGCAAAAGUAUACCUCAUGGGUUGUGGUAUUCAAGACGCAGCAUAUAAAAUACCUACCAUAAUGCUUCAGAGCAUAAUUCUUACUUCAUGUGAAUUAGAAAAUGAACACCAGAAAAACUAAGAGAUCUCUGCCUUGUCACUGGUAAAAACAUACGCAUCAUGAGUCAUUCUGACAAAGUGUAAGCUUUGUAAGACCACUAUUUAUCCCCUGUAUGUUUCAUGAAUGGGACUUACAUACUGGAUUGCUAAUAUUAUCAACCUCCUUGCAAGGAAGCUGUUGCUACCUUUAAGGCAAGUGAGGCCCAGAGAAGUUCAGUAUUUUACCCAUGGUCACAUGUGCAGUGGAAGAUGGAUGAGAGACUUGAGCCCGGGCUUUCUGAUUCCAAGGCUGUGCCUUCUCUAUACCGUCAGUUGCCUCCCUUUCUAAGAAUGGCGUUGCUUUGGGCAGAACAAAUUCCUCAACACGUUCUCAGUUACAUAUGUUCAAUCUAACUGGCAUAAGUGGAAGCUGGAGCAGGGAUUCUGUGGGGUGUGAUAAUGGGAUCUUGUGGCUGAAAAGCACAGCCAGAUCCAGGGCUUCAACAACGUCGCCGAGACUCUGUCUCUUUCCACCUGUUGUUCCUGCCCUUCUCUGAUGGAUGGGCUCUUCACUAUUGGAGGCAAAAUGGUCAUUGUUGGUUGUGCGUUAUCAGCUUUCCAUUUGCCAGUUAGAGCAAAGAGGGCCUUGCUCCUAGCAAUUCCAUCAAAAGUCCUGGGCUGAUGUUUAUGGCUCUUAAUGGUCUUGCUUGGAGCAUGUGCCUAUCUCUAAACUAAUCCCUGGGGCUGGAGGAUGGAAGUUGAGGGACAGUGGAAUAUGUUGAUUGGCAAGGCUUGGGAGAUGUGUCCAGGUGAACUCAAUGCAGAAAGGCAUGAUUCCUCAAGGAAAAUCAGGGCGCACUUACUAGUGGAAGGGGAAGUAGAUGCAGGUUAGGGAAACCUGUGGCUGUUCACCUUACAGUGCUUGAUUACAGCUCAAGUCUGGGUCAAAAUGAAGGGAGAUGUGGUGGGCAGCCGCAGCCCUCAGCAACACAAGCGGAGCACAGGAACACCUCAGGGUCUUCCAGUUCCCAUCUCAGAAGGGAGAAUGUGUGCAAGUGUGGCUAUGCCCAGAGCCAGCACAUGGAAGGCACCCAGAUCAACCAAAGUGAGAAAUGGAACUACAAGAAACACACCAAGGAAUUUCCUACCGACGCCUUUGGGGAUAUUCAGUUUGAGACACUGGGGAAGAAAGGGAAGUAUAUACGUCUGUCCUGCGACACGGACGCGGAAAUCCUUUACGAGCUGCUGACCCAGCACUGGCACCUGAAAACACCCAACCUGGUCAUUUCUGUGACCGGGGGCGCCAAGAACUUCGCCCUGAAGCCGCGCAUGCGCAAGAUCUUCAGCCGGCUCAUCUACAUCGCGCAGUCCAAAGGUGCUUGGAUUCUCACGGGAGGCACCCAUUAUGGCCUGAUGAAGUACAUCGGGGAGGUGGUGAGAGAUAACACCAUCAGCAGGAGUUCAGAGGAGAAUAUUGUGGCCAUUGGCAUAGCAGCUUGGGGCAUGGUCUCCAACCGGGACACCCUCAUCAGGAAUUGCGAUGCUGAGGGCUAUUUUUUAGCCCAGUACCUUAUGGAUGACUUCACAAGAGAUCCACUGUAUAUCCUGGACAACAACCACACACAUUUGCUGCUCGUGGACAAUGGCUGUCAUGGACAUCCCACUGUCGAAGCAAAGCUCCGGAAUCAGCUAGAGAAGUAUAUCUCUGAGCGCACUAUUCAAGAUUCCAACUAUGGUGGCAAGAUCCCCAUUGUGUGUUUUGCCCAAGGAGGUGGAAAAGAGACUUUGAAAGCCAUCAAUACCUCCAUCAAAAAUAAAAUUCCUUGUGUGGUGGUGGAAGGCUCGGGCCAGAUCGCUGAUGUGAUCGCUAGCCUGGUGGAGGUGGAGGAUGCCCUGACAUCUUCUGCCGUCAAGGAGAAGCUGGUGCGCUUUUUACCCCGCACGGUGUCCCGGCUGCCUGAGGAGGAGACUGAGAGUUGGAUCAAAUGGCUCAAAGAAAUUCUCGAAUGUUCUCACCUAUUAACAGUUAUUAAAAUGGAAGAAGCUGGGGAUGAAAUUGUGAGCAAUGCCAUCUCCUACGCUCUAUACAAAGCCUUCAGCACCAGUGAGCAAGACAAGGAUAACUGGAAUGGGCAGCUGAAGCUUCUGCUGGAGUGGAACCAGCUGGACUUAGCCAAUGAUGAGAUUUUCACCAAUGACCGCCGAUGGGAGUCUGCUGACCUUCAAGAAGUCAUGUUUACGGCUCUCAUAAAGGACAGACCCAAGUUUGUCCGCCUCUUUCUGGAGAAUGGCUUGAACCUACGGAAGUUUCUCACCCAUGAUGUCCUCACUGAACUCUUCUCCAACCACUUCAGCACGCUUGUGUACCGGAAUCUGCAGAUCGCCAAGAAUUCCUAUAAUGAUGCCCUCCUCACGUUUGUCUGGAAACUGGUUGCGAACUUCCGAAGAGGCUUCCGGAAGGAAGACAGAAAUGGCCGGGACGAGAUGGACAUAGAACUCCACGACGUGUCUCCUAUUACUCGGCACCCCCUGCAAGCUCUCUUCAUCUGGGCCAUUCUUCAGAAUAAGAAGGAACUCUCCAAAGUCAUUUGGGAGCAGACCAGGGGCUGCACUCUGGCAGCCCUGGGAGCCAGCAAGCUUCUGAAGACUCUGGCCAAAGUGAAGAACGACAUCAAUGCUGCUGGGGAGUCCGAGGAGCUGGCUAAUGAGUACGAGACCCGGGCUGUUGAGCUGUUCACUGAGUGUUACAGCAGCGAUGAAGACUUGGCAGAACAGCUGCUGGUCUAUUCCUGUGAAGCUUGGGGUGGAAGCAACUGUCUGGAGCUGGCGGUGGAGGCCACAGACCAGCAUUUCAUCGCCCAGCCUGGGGUCCAGAAUUUUCUUUCUAAGCAAUGGUAUGGAGAGAUUUCCCGAGACACCAAGAACUGGAAGAUUAUCCUGUGUCUGUUUAUUAUACCCUUGGUGGGCUGUGGCUUUGUAUCAUUUAGGAAGAAACCUGUCGACAAGCACAAGAAGCUGCUUUGGUACUAUGUGGCGUUCUUCACCUCCCCCUUCGUGGUCUUCUCCUGGAAUGUGGUCUUCUACAUCGCCUUCCUCCUGCUGUUUGCCUACGUGCUGCUCAUGGAUUUCCAUUCGGUGCCACACCCCCCCGAGCUGGUCCUGUACUCGCUGGUCUUUGUCCUCUUCUGUGAUGAAGUGAGACAGUGGUACGUAAAUGGGGUGAAUUAUUUUACUGACCUGUGGAAUGUGAUGGACACGCUGGGGCUUUUUUACUUCAUAGCAGGAAUUGUAUUUCGGCUCCACUCUUCUAAUAAAAGCUCUUUGUAUUCUGGACGAGUCAUUUUCUGUCUGGACUACAUUAUUUUCACUCUAAGAUUGAUCCACAUUUUUACUGUAAGCAGAAACUUAGGACCCAAGAUUAUAAUGCUGCAGAGGAUGCUGAUCGAUGUGUUCUUCUUCCUGUUCCUCUUUGCGGUGUGGAUGGUGGCCUUUGGCGUGGCCAGGCAAGGGAUCCUUAGGCAGAAUGAGCAGCGCUGGAGGUGGAUAUUCCGUUCGGUCAUCUACGAGCCCUACCUGGCCAUGUUCGGCCAGGUGCCCAGUGACGUGGAUGGUACCACGUAUGACUUUGCCCACUGCACCUUCACUGGGAAUGAGUCCAAGCCACUGUGUGUGGAGCUGGAUGAGCACAACCUGCCCCGGUUCCCCGAGUGGAUCACCAUCCCCCUGGUGUGCAUCUACAUGUUAUCCACCAACAUCCUGCUGGUCAACCUGCUGGUCGCCAUGUUUGGCUACACGGUGGGCACCGUCCAGGAGAACAAUGACCAGGUCUGGAAGUUCCAGAGGUACUUCCUGGUGCAGGAGUACUGCAGCCGCCUCAAUAUCCCCUUCCCCUUCAUCGUCUUCGCUUACUUCUACAUGGUGGUGAAGAAGUGCUUCAAGUGUUGCUGCAAGGAGAAAAACAUGGAGUCUUCUGUCUGCUGUUUCAAAAAUGAAGACAAUGAGACUCUGGCAUGGGAGGGUGUCAUGAAGGAAAACUACCUUGUCAAGAUCAACACAAAAGCCAACGACACCUCAGAGGAAAUGAGGCAUCGAUUUAGACAACUGGAUACAAAGAUCAUAUUAAGGAAUGCUGAUGAACAAUUUUGCUAUCGACUACUAAAUGAGAGAUUUUCAGACCCCUGGGUACAUGGUGGAUGAUUUUAAAUCACCCUAGUGUGCUGAGACCUUGAGAAUAAAGUGUGUGAUUGGUUUCAUACUUGAAGACGGAUAUAAAGGAAGAAUAUUUCCUUUAUGUGUUUCUCCAGAAUGGUGCCUGUUUCUCUCUGUGUCUCAAUGCCUGGGACUGGAGGUUGAUAGUUUAAGUGUGUUCUUACCGCCUCCUUUUUCCUUUAAUCUUAUUUUUGAUGAACACAUAUAUAGGAGAACAUCUAUCCUAUGAAUAAGAACCUGGUCAUGCUUUACUCCUGUAUUGUUAUUUUGUUCAUUUCCAAUUGAUUCUCUACUUUUCCCUUUUUUGUAUUAUGUGACUAAUUAGUUGGCAUAUUGUUAAAAGUCUCUCAAAUUAGGCCAGAUUCUAAAACAUGCUGCAGCAAGAGGACCCCGCUCUCUUCAGGAAAAGUGUUUUCAUUUCUCAGGAUGCUUCUUACCUGUCAGAGGAGGUGACAAGGCAGUCUCUUGCUCUCUUGGACUCACCAGGCUCCUAUUGAAGGAACCACCCCCAUUCCUAAAUAUGUGAAAAGUCGCCCAAAAUGCAACCUUGAAAGGCACUACUGACUUUGUUCUUAUUGGAUACUCCUCUUAUUAUUUUUCCAUUAAAAAUAAUAGCUGGCUAUUAUAGAAAAUUUAGACCAUACAGAGAUGUAGAAAGAACAUAAAUUGUCCCCAUUACCUUAAGGUAAUCACUGCUAACAAUUUCUGGAUGGUUUUUCAAGUCUAUUUUUUUUCUAUGUAUGUCUCAAUUCUCUUUCAAAAUUUUACAGAAUGUUAUCAUACUACAUAUAUACUUUUUAUGUAAGCUUUUUCACUUAGUAUUUUAUCAAAUAUGUUUUUAUUAUAUUCAUAGCCUUCUUAAACAUUAUAUCAAUAAUUGCAUAAUAGGCAACCUCUAGCGAUUACCAUAAUUUUGCUCAUUGAAGGCUAUCUCCAGUUGAUCAUUGGGAUGAGCAUCUUUGUGCAUGAAUCCUAUUGCUGUAUUUGGGAAAAUUUUCCAAGGUUAGAUUCCAAUAAAUAUCUAUUUAUUAUUAAAUAUUAAAAUAUCUAUUUAUUAUUAAAACCAUUUAUAAGGCUUUUUCAUAAAUGUAUAGCAAAUAGGAAUUAUUAACUUGAGCAUAAGAUAUGAGAUACAUGAACCUGAACUAUUAAAAUAAAAUAUUAUAUUUAACCCUUAGUUUAAGAAGAAGUCAAUAUGCUUAUUUAAAUAUUAUGGAUGGUGGGCAGAUCACUUGAGGUCAGGAGUUCGAGACCAGCCUGGCCAACAUGGCAAAACCACAUCUCUACUAAAAAUAAAAAAAUUAGCUGGGUGUGGUGGUGCACUCCUGUAAUCCCAGCUACUCAGAAGGCUGAGGUACAAGAAUUGCUGGAACCUGGGAGGCGGAGGUUGCAGUGAACCAAGAUUGCACCACUGCACUCCAGCCGGGGUGACAGAGUGAGACUCCGACUGAAAAUAAAUAAAUAAAUAAAUAAAUAAAUAAAUAAAUAUUAUGGAUGGUGAAGGGAAUGGUAUAGAAUUGGAGAGAUUAUCUUACUGAACACCUGUAGUCCCAGCUUUCUCUGGAAGUGGUCGUAUUUGAGCAGGAUGUGCACAAGGCAAUUGAAAUGCCCAUAAUUAGUUUCUCAGCUUUGAAUACACUAUAAACUCACUGGCUGAAGGAGGAAAUUUUAGAAGGAAGCUACUAAAAGAUCUAAUUUGAAAAACUACAAAAGCAUUAACUAAAAAAGUUUAUUUUCCUUUUGUCUGGGCAGUAGUGAAAAUAACUACUCACAACAUUCACUAUGUUUGCAAGGAAUUAACACAAAUAAAAGAUGCCUUUUUACUUAAACACCAAGACAGAAAACUUGCCCAAUACUGAGAAGCAACUUGCAUUAGAGAGGGAACUGUUAAAUGUUUUCAACCCAGUUCAUCUGGUGGAUGUUUUUGCAGGUUACUCUGAGAAUUUUGCUUAUGAAAAAUCAUUAUUUUUAGUGUAGUUCACAAUAAUGUAUUGAACAUACUUCUAAUCAAAGGUGCUAUGUCCUUGUGUAUGGUACUAAAUGUGUCCUGUGUACUUUUGCACAACUGAGAAUCCUGCAGCUUGGUUUAAUGAGUGUGUUCAUGAAAUAAAUAAUGGAGGAAUUGUCA